CCUGGUCCGACCCCCAGUGGCACUAACGUGGGAUCCUCAGGGCGCUCUCCCAGCAAAGCAGUGGCCGCCCGGGCGGCGGGAUCCACUGUCCGGCAGAGGUAAGGAACCCUGCAGUUCGUUCGCUUCCAGACUCGGAGAUAGGACCCAGAACCUCGCUGAUUCUGGGGUGGAGACCCUAGCAUGUGAAGAUUGACAAAGGCAAAAUGAGCUUCUAGUGACGUGGCCGUGGGAGUAGUUAAAGGCCUUUUGGGAGGAAGGCGACAUUUUUUUUCUCGUUGCUCAGUUUAGGGCACUACUCUUAAAAAAGGAAAGUUAACAAACUGGAAUAGAGUCAGAGAUAACUUUGAGAAAACCGAUGUCAUUAAACUGGUGUCUCUGGACCUGAGGUUUGCACUCACAUUUCCAUCUGGCGGCCCCAUAAGCAAUCUGUCCUACAGAUAACUCGUCCUACACAAAACUUAGUCUCUUUUCAGCUCAGCUCUCUCACUCUCAAUUAUAUCUCCUUACUUCCAUAUGGCACUGUUGUACACUCAUUUACUCAGAGCCAGAAACGUCAGCGUCAUCUUGGAUUUUUCUUAUGCUCUUUCUCUCUCUAGUCAUAUGCCAGACUUUAAACUCUGCUUGAAAGCUUUCUCAUAAGCUCUUUCCUUUUCCCUUUCUACUGCUUUGCAUUUGCUACUUAACCCUUUUCUUCAGGCUGUUUGCUUUCCAGUCCAUCGUUCGCUCUGCUGUUACUCUUCUGCGUAGUUUCUGUUACUUGUUGCUGAACUAAAAAAAACAAACAAACAAAAAAAAAAAACCGGGGGGAUACCAAAGCUCUUAGUGGUCAUUUCAGCCUAACCUUUCUUUUUCCUUUUUUUUUUUUUGGGAUGGAAUCUCACUCUGUCGCCCAGGCUGGAGUGCAGUGGCACGAUCUCGGCUCACUACAGCCUUUGCCUCCAGAGUUCAAGCAAUUCUCCUGCCUCAGCCUCCUGAGUAGCUGAGACUGCAGGCACGUGCCACCACACCCAGCUAAUUUUUUGUAUUUUUAGUAGAGACGGGGUUUCACCAUGUUAGCCAGGAUGGUCUCGAUCUCCUGACCUUGUGAUCCUCCGUCUCUGCCUCCAAAAGUGCUGGAAUUACAGGCGUGAGCCACUGCGCCCGGCCUUCAGCCUAAUCUUUCUUUGCUGUCCUAUGAUCCAGCACUCGUGAACCCAUUACUGUUUUCUGAAUUCACAAACUUUCUCCCUCAUCUCAAGGCAAAUUUCUACUUAUUUUCCAAGACUAAGCUCAGGGGUUAUUUCCUCUUGAGGCCUUCUCUGUCUGUAAGCAGCAGUAGCUACUAGUUUUCCCUUUUGCCCCCAUAGCAUUUUGUUCAUAUCAUUAUAAGACCAGUGAUGUUUCCAUAUUUAUCUCCUUCAUUAGACUUUAACAGAGAACCUGCUCAAGUCAUUUCUAUCCCAGGUACCCACCAUAAGGCAUGACACAAUAAAUAAUGACUGAAGGAAGGAAUCAAGCAACCAAGUUGUUUUGGGAUUUUUGAAGGAACUAGUGGGGUUUUAUCUAGGGAGGAAAAAAUCUUGAACACAUGCAUGGAAACUUCUGAAGGAUGUGAAGAGGGAUGUGACAUUUUCUGGCUGCAACAGGAAAAAUGCCAGCUGUGGGACAAGGAGUGCAGGCCGCACAACCUCGGCAGGCACCGGGGGGAUGUGGCGAUUCUACACAGAAGAUUCACCUGGGCUCAAAGUUGGCCCUGUUCCAGUAUUGGUUAUGAGUCUUCUGUUCAUCGCUUCUGUAUUUAUGUUGCACAUUUGGGGCAAGUACACUCGUUCGUAGAUUCAGUUACAUCCAUCUGUCAUCUGAAGAAGGAGGAAAAAACCCAACAUUUCUUGGACCAAAAGUAUAGUGACUAUCUGUUCAUGAGAGAAAUUUUCUGUAAGCUUGCUGUUUUACAGGGGAUUUAUCAAUAAUUGAUUUUGAGGAAUCAGUUUUUUUCUAUGGCUAAUAAACUUUUUAAUUCACUUAUA